GUGUACUUCCGCUGCAGGAGGGCGAAGCAGCCGUCAUCUAUCCCCUCUGGGAGGUGAGUCAGCGCGGAACCUCUGCAUCUACGGCGAGCUUUCCUGGCCUGGGCGUUGGACUCGCAGGUGCCUGCCCUCGCUCUCAGUGAAGGGAAGUCGCAGAGGGCGGGGACGACGGUUUGCUUGCCCUUUGUUUUUAGGGCGGUGCAUGGGUCUCCAAGUUGGGAAUGGCUCCUGGUCGCACGUUUGGUUUGAAGGUCUCCCGGGCGCUCAAGUUCCCUCGCCUUCCCCACCUUCCACACGCUCUGCUGUCUUCUGGCAAUAUAAUCUUGUUCUGCCUUCCCAGGACCCUGCCCUUCCCCAGAAGGAGCAGGAGAAAAUGACCAAGUUUCAGGAGAUGGUGACAUUCAAGGAUGUGGCUGUGGUCUUCACCAGGGAGGAGCUGGGGUUGCUGGACCUUGCCCAGAGAAAGCUGUACCAAGAUGUGAUGCUGGAGAACUUCAGGAACCUGCUGUCAGUGGGCUAUCAACCCUUCAAACUAGAUGUGAUAUUACAGUUGGGAAAAGAAGACAAGCUUCGGAUGAUGGAGACAGAAAUCCAAGGAGAUGGGUGUUCAGGUGAGAACCAUGGAGCUCUGAGUCUUUGCGGGGUACAGCCUAGUCCUCUCCUCCUCACCACCUCCUCAGCCACCAGCCUGGCCCAAGACCCCAGAAUUCAUCGCCCUGGUUUACUGCAGCAGCUUGCACAUGACCUUCCUCCUUCUACCUCCCUCCAGUCCAUUCUCCACAUAGCCAGAUCAUGACACAAGAAUCAAAAUGAGAUAGAUACCCUUCAAGAAGUAAGAUUAAGAUUCCUUUCAUAUGAAGACCUUAUAUGCUGGCAAAUAUGGGAACAAUUUACAAGUAAAUUAACCAGUAAUCAAGACCUAAUAAUAAAUCUUCAAGGCAAGAGGUCCAAGUUGCUAAAACAAGGUGAUUCCCCCUGUCAGGUGUGGACAGGAGAAUCUAGUCAGGUCUCUGAAGAUGAGAACUAUGUAAUAAAGCUACAAGGGGAGAGUUCAAAUAGCAUAAAAAAUCAAGAGCUUCCAUUGAGGACCACCUGGGAUUUCUGGAGGAAAAUGUAUCUGAGAGAACCACAGAAUUAUCAGAGUAGGUGUCAGCAAAUUGAUGUAAAAAAUAAGCUCUGUAAAUGUGAUCAUUGUGUUAGGCAAAGAAUUGCUCAUCAACAUGAUGAUCAUGGAGUACACAAAAGAGAGAAAGCUUUUAGCCACAAUAAUUGUGGAAAAGACUGUGUGAAGGAAUCAUCCCAGCAUAGCAUAAUCCAAUCAGGAGAGCAAACCUCUGAUGAAAAUGGAAAAGGCUUAAGUGUUGGCUCUAAUCUUGAACUUCACCAGCAACUACACUUAAGAGACAAGCCUCAUGUAAAUGUUGAGUACGGGAAGGGCAUAGGUUACAGCUCAGGGCUUCCCAGGCAUCAGUGUUUCCACAUAGGAGAGAAAUGCUAUAGGAAUGGUGACAGUGGUGAGGGCUUCAGUCAGGGCUCACAUCUGCAACCUCAUCAGAGAGUCAGCACAGGAGAGAACCUCUACAGAUGUCAGGUAUAUGCCCGGAGCUCCAACCAGAACUCCUGUCUUCCCUCUCAUGAGCUUACUCACCCAGGAGAGAAGUUGUGUACAUGUGGCAGGUGUGGGAAGGGCUUCCAUCAUAGCUUAGAUUUUGACAUUCACUGUGUAGACAGUGCUGGAGAGAGAGCCUGUAAAUGUGAUGUAUAUGAUAAAGGCUUCAGUCAGACAUCACAACUUCAAGCCCAUCAGAGAGGUCACUCUAGAGACAAGACAUACAAAUGGGAAGUAAGUGACAGGAUAUUUAAUAGGAAUUCUGGUCUUCACCAGAGAGUUCACACUGGAGAGAAACCAUAUAAAUGUGAGGUAUGUGAUAAGGGCUUCAGUAAGGCCUCAAAUCUUCAAGCCCAUCAGAGAAUCCACACUGGAGAGAAACCCUACAAAUGUGAUGUGUGUGAUAAGAACUUCAGCCGUAAUUCCCACCUUCAGGCCCAUCAGAGAGUCCAUACAGGAGAGAAACCCUACAAAUGUGACACAUGUGGGAAGGACUUCAGUCAGAUCUCUCAUCUUCAGGCCCAUCAGAGAGUUCACAAAGGAGAGAAGCCAUACAAAUGUGAGACAUGUGGGAAGGGCUUUAGUCAGAGUUCGCAUCUCCAAGACCAUCAGCAAGUCCAUACUGGAGAGAAUCCCUACAAAUGUGAUGUGUGUGGGAAAGGCUUCAGUUGGAGUUCACAUCUUCAAGCCCAUCAGAGAGUCCACACAGGAGAGAAACCAUACAAAUGUGAAGAAUGUAGGAAAGGCUUCAUCUGGAACUCAUAUCUUCAUGUUCAUCAGAGGAUCCACACGGGAGAGAAACCCUAUAAAUGUGGCAUGUGUGGUAAGAGCUUCAGUCAGACUUCACAUCUUCAAGCCCAUCAGAGAGUCCAUACUGGAGAGAAACCAUACAAAUGUUUUGUGUGUGGUAAGGGCUUUAGUAAGAGUUCGUUGUCUUCAGAUUCAUCAGAGAGUCCAUGAUGGUGAUGAAUCUAUUAAUCAUGAUGAGUGUGAUAGGGGUGCUCUUCAAGACUUAGACUUCCCAUUUUCCUCAGAAAAUCCACACAGCACAGAAUAUUUAUAAAAUGUCAUGUUUUAAGAAUUCAUGAGCUGAGUUUUUAUAGUUAUCUGAAUUCCAUUGAAGAAAACCUAUUUUUGUAUGAAUAUGACCAGUUUCAAGCAGAGCCCAAAAUGUCACAGUUGUCAAGAGAACACACAACAGAGAAACCCUAUAAAGAAUGAUACAAUAUGUUUCAAUCAGAACCUUCACAUCCAAUAAGCAAUAUGCAGGAGUGAAGCCUUCAAAAUGAUAAGUAAGGUCAGAAUUUAGCAAAAGUAUAAUGAGGGACAUGACAAAAUCUGUGUCCACUAGAAUCUAAGCUCCAUGCAGGAACAUUGUUUACUGCUGCAUGAUCGUGACCUUGAACAAGUACCUAAGAAAUAGUGGCUUCCCUGGAAUUGUUUAACUUGAUAGGAAAAAUCUAUCAUAUAUAGGACAUAUAUUUGAAUAUUUUAGUGAGCUCAGCCCCAAUUCGUCAUUAUAAUUGUACUGGGAAAAGGAUUCUUGCAAGAAGCCUUAAAAUGAAUUCAAGGAAAUGACAUUUAAUUAAAACACAUAAAACCAA